GCCCCGGCUCAGCACCUCGGAGAGCUCCCUCCCCGGCCUUGUUUUGCUCUGGCAUCGCCGCCGGGGGAGGGAGCGAGGGGGCCGGGCACCGGGCGCAAAGGCAGGGGGAUGGCCAUGGAAGGGUUGAGGGGCCCCGUCGGACAGAGGGCCCAGCCGUGAUCCAGCGACGGGUUUGGGGCUCCGGGAGGGGUGGGGGGGCAGCGGGCGGCGGCAGCAGUGGCCGCACAUCUGGAUGGAAGCGAGCUUUGUCCAGACCACCAUGGCUCUGGGGCUGUCCUCCAAGAAAGCGUCCUCUCGCAACGUGGCUGUGGAGCGUAAGAACCUGAUCACCGUGUGCAGGUUCUCUGUGAAAACGCUGCUGGAGAAGUACACAGCGGAGCCCAUCGAUGACUCAUCGGAGGAGUUUGUCAAUUUUGCAGCCAUUUUAGAGCAGAUCCUCAGCCACCGCUUCAAAGCCUGUGCCCCAGCAGGUCCAGUGAGCUGGUUCAGCUCAGACGGGCAGCGGGGCUUUUGGGACUAUAUCCGGCUGGCCUGCAGCAAAGUGCCCAACAACUGUGUGAGCAGCAUCGAGAACAUGGAGAACAUCAGCACAGCCCGGGCCAAGGGCCGGGCAUGGAUCCGGGUGGCACUGAUGGAGAAGCGCAUGUCAGAAUACAUCACCACGGCUCUGCGUGACACCCGGACCACCAGACGGUUCUAUGACUCUGGAGCCAUCAUGCUGCGGGAUGAAGCCACCAUCCUCACCGGAAUGCUGAUCGGACUGAGCGCCAUCGACUUCAGCUUCUGUCUAAAGGGGGAAGUCCUGGACGGGAAGACCCCCGUGGUCAUCGAUUACACGCCCUACCUAAAGUUCACGCAGAGCUACGACUACCUGACGGACGAGGAGGAGCGGCACAGCGCCGAGAGCAGCACGAGCGAGGACAACUCGCCCGAGCACCCGUACCUCCCGCUCGUCACCGAUGAGGACAGCUGGUACAGCAAGUGGCACAAGAUGGAGCAGAAGUUCCGCAUCGUCUACGCGCAGAAGGGCUACCUGGAGGAGCUGGUGCGUCUGCGCGAGUCGCAGCUGAAGGACCUGGAGGCGGAGAACCGGCGGCUUCAGCUGCAGCUGGAGGAGGCGGCGGCGCAGAACCAGCGCGAGAAACGGGAGCUGGAAGGCGUGAUCCUGGAGCUGCAGGAGCAGCUGACAGGUCUGAUCCCCAGUGACCACGCCCCUCUGGCCCAGGGUUCCAAGGAGCUCACUACACCCCUGGUCAAUCAAUGGCCCUCACUGGGAACGCUUAAUGGGGCCGAGGGCGCCAGCAACUCCAAGCUCUACCGGAGACACAGCUUCAUGAGCACGGAGCCGCUGUCAGCUGAAGCCAGUCUGAGCUCGGACUCCCAGCGCCUGGGAGAGGGCACGCGGGACGAGGAGCCCUGGGGUCCCAUCGAGACGGAGUUUCGCCAGGCUGGUCUCGAACUCCUGACCUCAAGUGAUUCACCCACCUUGGCCUCCCAAAGUGCUGGGAUUACAGGGAAGGACCCCACGCCCUCCAUGCUGGGCCUCUGCGGCUCCCUGGCCUCCAUUCCCAGCUGCAAGUCCCUGGCGAGCUUCAAAUCCAACGAGUGCCUGGUGAGCGACAGUCCCGAGGGCAGCCCAGCACUGAGCCCCAGCUGAGGAACAGCAUGGGCAGUGCCAGCCCCACCUGCCAGGGGCCAUGGACACCUGCCACCUUUCUUCAACAAGAGUCCCCCAAUCCAGGCUACCCUUCCAGAGAACGCUACCCACCCAGCCAGGGUUCUCUCGGGGAAGAUCUCGUCUGCUCACCUUAGCUUUCUGCCUUGGCAGCACGGGCUGCGGAAGAAAGCACGCUGGGCCAGGAGGCAGGGGUGCCCAAGCCACAGGGAGCCCCUGGGGAAGCCUGCUCCAUUCUUCUGGUGACCUUGGCGCUCCUUCACUCAUCUCCCCUGCCCCCUCAGGAACUGGUGGCCCAGCUUCCACACCCCCACCUCCCAGUCUCUAGCCUCUCCAUCUGUCUGUGUAUGGCCUGGAGUCACUCCUUCCUCAGCCCCCAGGGCAAGAGAGCUCAAAUAAAAACCAGAGGACUGA